AAUCCCCGCGGGGACCCGGAGCGCGGCUGCCGGUCUACGCCCUCUCUCCUGCCGCUCUCGCGGCGCAGCCCGGCCGGGGGCCCCCGCGCGCCGGCAGCUCUAGGGGCGAGCGCGGCGCGCUGACUGGGCGUGCUCAGCCGCGGAGCGCCCGGGCGCCGCUAGAGCCAAGCGCAUGCACUCGCCGGGCCGGGCCGUCCAGGGGCGCAGCGCGCAGGGGGCCGCUCUAGCCGACGCCCUGGCCAGUCUGGGCAGGACGCGGGCCAGGAUGGCCUCCCUCACCGCAUACGACAAAGAUGUGAGCAGCGGAAGUUAUAACCUUUCCUCUGCAACGACGGGCAGCUACUACAGUUGUGUCAGCCAGAUCACCAUAGGUUAUGACGUUGCGGGGCCUGUGGCAAUUGGGCUUACCCACUGGAAAAAUCCAUACGUACAAGGCAGACCAACCCUCCCAUCAGAUCUGCCUCUCUUCGUCUCCAAAGAUGCAGGCAUCCCUGUGUACCACCGAUCCUUCACCCGCAAGACUGACCAGGCCACACCUUUGUCCUGUCCAGCCUCACUGUCUAUCACUCCAGUGCCUUCUUACAGCAGUAGCAGCCAGGAAACCCUGAGUCAAGACACAACAGGUUUAAGUUUAUCUAUUCAUGGGGCUGAAAAGCGUUUGCAAAUCCAUCAACGGCGAAGUGUGGCAAGCCGCCCAGCGUCACGUCGUCGCCUGCCUGUGGUCAGGCAUUCCUCACUCCCACCAGGCAGAAGGUCAAUAAAAAUGGAGGCAAGCUCUUCUGGAAUCACUAAUGGAAAAACCAAAGUCUUCCACCCAGAAGGAGGUGUGGAUUUGCAAGGCUACCAGCUGGAUAUGCAAAUACUACCUGACGGGCCAAAGAGUGAUGUGGACUUUUCAGAGAUUCUUAAUGCAAUACAAGAAAUGGCCAAGGAUGUCAAUAUUCUUUUUGAUGAAUUAGAAGCUGUCAGCAGUCCUUGCAAAGAUGACGAUUCUCUUCUUCACCCUGGAAACCUGACUAGUACUUCAGAUGAUGCCAGCAGAUUGGAAGCCGGGGGAGAGACAGUGCCAGAAAGAAACAAAUCAAAUGGACUUUACUUUCGAGAUGGAAAGUGUCGAAUUGACUACAUCCUUGUGUACAGAAAAUCCAACCCCCAGACUGAAAAGAGAGAAGUAUUUGAAAGAAACAUUAGAGCAGAAGGAUUGCAAAUGGAGAAAGAGUCCUCUCUAAUAAAUAGUGACAUUAUCUUUGUGAAGUUGCAUGCCCCAUGGGAAGUCCUUGGAAGAUAUGCAGAACAAAUGAAUGUAAGAAUGCCUUUCAGGAGAAAAAUCUAUUACCUGCCCCGCCGUUACAAGUUCAUGAGCAGGAUCGAUAAACAAAUAAGCAGGUUUCGGAGAUGGUUACCUAAGAAGCCAAUGAGGCUGGACAAGGAGACACUGCCAGACCUGGAGGAGAAUGACUGCUACACUGCCCCUUUCAGCCAGCAAAGGAUCCAUCACUUCAUCAUACACAACAAAGAAACGUUCUUCAACAAUGCCACAAGAAGUAGAAUCGUGCAUCACAUUUUACAAAGAAUAAAAUAUGAAGAAGGAAAAAACAAGAUUGGUCUGAAUCGUUUGCUUACCAAUGGCUCCUAUGAAGCUGCGUUUCCCCUGCAUGAGGGAAGUUAUAGAAGUAAAAACUCCAUUCGAACCCAUGGAGCAGAAAACCACCGACAUCUACUCUAUGAGUGCUGGGCCUCCUGGGGCGUGUGGUAUAAAUACCAACCUUUGGAUCUUGUAAGGCGGUACUUUGGAGAGAAGAUUGGGUUAUAUUUUGCCUGGUUGGGCUGGUACACCGGCAUGCUCUUCCCAGCUGCCUUCAUUGGAUUGUUUGUCUUUUUGUAUGGCGUCACCACUCUGGAUCACAGCCAAGUCAGUAAAGAAGUCUGCCAAGCUACAGAUAUCAUCAUGUGUCCUGUGUGUGAUAAAUACUGUCCAUUCAUGAGGCUGUCAGACAGCUGUGUAUAUGCCAAGGUAACCCACCUUUUUGACAAUGGAGCCACUGUCUUCUUUGCUGUUUUCAUGGCAGUCUGGGAGACUGUCAAAGGAAAAUUGUCCCACCCAUCACAGCUCUGUUGAAGGGACAUGUUUUGAACCCCAUGACUCCAGUCCCUCUCAGCCAGUAAGCAUUUGAACCAAGAUCAGUCAAACCACAGGUUGGUGAGUGGCCUGGGAAAAGGCCUGAGGUUCUGCCCAGACAAGGACUGGUAGGGCCACCCAGAUUCUUAUUCUCCAGAAUGUGGACUAGAAAAUGUAAAGGGAAAUAGGGAGUUAGCAGCAGGAAUGGACACUGAAAAAUACAGAGGGCAGGAGGGAGGGAGAAAAAGAAAGAUUAAAAUUGACCAUUGGGUAGAAGUAGGGACCAGGAGGAAUUAGGAGGCUGAAGUUAUGAGAAUCAGAACCUAGAAAUAGAUAGAAGCAAAGAACUAGUGGAAAAAUUAGAGGGCGAAAAAGCCAACUGGGAGAAAAUGUAAGACAACCAGAGGGAAGCAAAGAGAGAAUAUAGCCAAGUCAUGUUACUAGUGGAGUGUCAGGAUGAAGACCCAGACUCUCUUGUGGCUGAGGCCUCUCUCAAGCUUCGGGCUUCCAUAUCCUGUCUCUGAACAGGCCAUGUAUUUUUUCCUGUAGGAUUCCUGCCUCCCUUGGUGGACCUUGUGAAAAGCUUUCACUGUUCAUGCUACCCUUAAUGCUUCUCUGUCCCUUGCAAACAAACUAACCCUAACAGAAUUUUGAUUACAGGCCUGAGCUCUCAGAUAAAGAAUGCGUAUAUAGUUUUACUAGAAUCUAUUAGUAUCAUACACCGUGAUUCGGAUAAGCCAUAUAAUGCUUAAGCUUUGCCAUGGUCACAAAUGAGGGGACUCUGGAAAUAUAUUCAUUUCCUAAACCAGUAUUAUAAAUACUAAAUGUAUUCUGUAAACCUUAAUGUAUAUAGUAUUCUGUAAACGUAAAUACUAAAUGUAUAUUGUAAACCUAAAUGUAUUCAUUUCCUAAACUUUUCAGGUCAUAGCACACAUAAAAAUGAAAAUAUUUACACAGCAGCUGCUGUACAUGGAGGAGCCUCCUCAUGGCCAUGGAUAGGGCUGUCCCAAACACCCCAGCCUCAGAAGCCACAAGGGUUGAAAGGGGCAUUAUUGUUAUUCCUGGCAUAGGCAUUUGGAAGUUCUGCCUUGGGCUGCUAAUUUACUGUGCAAUGAGUUAAUGCUUCUAUAUAAGAGUGGUAUCCUGGUGGUAUCCUGGAAGAAUUAAAACACAAAACUUCCUUACCCACUUCAAUAUUUCACCAAUUUCAAAUAUACUUUGAAUUAAAUAAUGGUUUCUUCUCACAGUUUACCUCCUGAGACUACAUAGAAGUAAAUUUUUGUAUGAUGACAUUUGUUCAUAAGGCAGAGGUUAUUACUCUCCCCCACUACCUCCAUUAUAAAAUGGAUUGCAUACCCUCUUUGCAAGUUGUGUUUUAUGUUAUAGAUGACAAAUAGGUUUUGUUUUAUCCCCUUGCCAACCUCAGCUGAUUGGUGCUGGCUGCCUGGAGCAUGGAGUUGAGAAGUUUCUGAGGUUGAAAGUGGGUGGAUUGGAGAUUUAACAGCCCUUGUGGUUUGGAGUAUACUUUGUAAGACUCUGAUGGAUGUUUUAUAAUAAACUUUGGGCACAGAGGAACAUUUUAGGGCCAUUCCAGGCAAGACAUGCCUGGAAUAAUUCACCCUCUGAAUUGCUUUGUCUUAGAUGACAACUUAUUGCUUAAAUCCCACAUUAUUCCCAGAAAUGUGCUAGUUUGAGAAAAAGAAUGAGUUGCCCCAAGUGUUUCUUUGUAGAUAGAGAUAAUGCCUUUUGCAGAAAUCUGAAAGAGUCAACAAUAUUAACAGUUAUAUUAAUAGCAUUCAUUUCCGAGGGAUUACUAUGUACUAAAUGCAGUCCUAAGCAUUGCCCAUGUAUCAUCUCAUUUAAUCUCUCCAGCAAGCUUUUAAAAAGGUACUGUUCUUAUCCUCAUAUGACAGAUAAGGAAACUGCAGCAGUAGCUAGAAAGUGGCAAAGCCAAGAGUUAAACUGGGCAGUGUGAGCUCCUCUGCUCUACUGCUAGAAUCAGGUAUUGUUUGUUACCAUUUCCUUCUGUUUUAGAGACCUGAACCUUAAAAUAAAGGACUGCUAUGCCUGUCCUGAGCCUCAUUUAUCCUGCUUUGAGACAGUAAUGUUCUAUAAAAAUGUGUCAGUUCUAAUGGAGCUCAGUUUAAUGGUCUCAGGAUCAUCUCUUAUGAUCGACAAGUUACAGCAUUAAAGAAAACAAAUGCACUCUAUUUUCAGGAAAUUGCUAGAUAUGGAGCUGAUGAGAACAGAUGUAAGUGGUUUACAAGACUUCUGAAGGGCUGGGCUUGACGUGUUCAUUUUGUUACCUUUGCUUUGUGUGUUCACCGGAAAAAAAUAAUAAGGCUCCAUCUGUAACCAGUUUGUAGCAACUGGGAGGGCCUUGGCAUUGGGUUAGGAAUCCUGACAGAACUCUACUACCUUUGUUCAGGUCACGUCUGUGUGAGUGCAGGGCUCCCUCGGGAUCCCUGAGGUAUGCUGUGAGCCUGGGUCUCGGCUGGAAUUACAGUGUGGCUCAUUCCUCAAUGCUCAUUUUUGUUCAGAAAGGUCCAAGGGUCAGAAUGAUUAUGGACUAAAUAACUCCUCUCCCGAGGGAAAAAAUGAGUCAUCAGGGAACUAGAUGUUGGCAGAGACCUGUCGGGGAAACAGAUUAUUUCCCUCUGUUCUGUUUCUGGUUUGGUUUGUUUUUUUUCUCUCUCUCCCCCUUGUUUUUCAUUUUUUACUUCUAGGAUUGCCAAAAGUUAAGUUAUCCCCAGUAAACACACCAAGCAAGAUCCACAAAGCUCUUUAAUCAAAAUGACAAGAUGGUAAUUAUUUAGUGUGAUCCUGUUAGUAAUUGGUGAAUGAAGUAUGUCUCAUUUAAAAAAAUAAAUUUUGCAAGAAUCAGCCUUUUGUUUCUAGAUAUUUAUGCUAACUUUAUAUUUUAUAGUCUUAUCUACAUGUUCCACAAAAAAAUGGUAAUUGUAUGUUGAAAAAGGUACACAUUUACUAAAGGCCUACCAUGUUUGUAUGCACAUUCACAUAGGAUACCUCAUCAAUUUCUCAUCACCCAUUAGAAAGAAAUUACUAACCUCAUUUUAUAGAUGAGGAUACUGAGGCUCAGAGAGGUUAUGCAACUUGCCCAGGAUUCCAGUAGCUGAUAAGGUGUGGAGCCUAAACUUUAAACCAGAUCUGGUCUGUUUCACUCCAGAGUCAUUCCAAAGUGUGUCCACCAUGUUGUGCAUCUUCUGUGAAGUGUGUCAAUUAAGAUCUCAUUAACUCAUACACAAAAAUGAGUUAGAUGUGAUCUCUGCUUUCAAAAAUCUCAGUAUAUUAAAGAAGCGUUGAUAAUUAUAAUACAGGGCAAGUCCAAUUUACAAUAGGCCAAUGAGGGUUUAUGUAGUCAACUUCCUGAGGCAAAAGGAAAAGCAGAAAAGGUUCACCCAAGAAGAGAUAUUGGAAAGAAGUCUUAGCUUUGCCAGGCAGAGUAGUGGGGUUGGAAGGAGACAUAGAUAACAUUCUUAGGUGACAAGAGUAUUUGUAAAGCUCUGAAAAGGAAGAAUUGGCUGUUCAGAGUGAUAGGGAGGUUGAGUGUGUAUUAGUUUCCUAGGACUGCUGUAACAUAGUACUACAA